CUCUUACCGCCAUGGAGUUCGACCUGGGAGCAGCCCUGGAGCCCACCUCCCAGAAGCCCGGUGUGGGGGCGGGCCACGGGGGAGAUCCCAAGCUCAGUCCCCACAAAGUUCAGGGCCGGUCGGAGGCAGGGGCAGGUCCGGGUCCAAAGGCCUCCAACUUCAGGGGGCUGGGUAAGGGGCGCCGCCUCACUGCCGCACCUCCAUCCAGCAAGGACACCACAGCUCUUCCGACUCCAGCAGCAGCUCCAGCGAUUCGGACACGGAUGUGAAGUCCCACGCUGCUGGCUCCAAGCAGCACGAGAGCAUCCCGGGCAAGGCCAAGAAGCCCAAAGUGAAGAAGAAGGAGAAGGGCAAGAAGGAGAAGGGCAAGAAGAAGGAGGCUCCCCACUGAAGGGCCCUGGACAGGGCUCAUUAAACCUUCCUCUCUGCCUUC